GGAAGUGGAGGCCGGAGCCUGGGACACCGCCGGCGGGGAGAGAAGCGGAUCCCGUCCGAGCCCCGGCCCCAAGUAACGCCGCCGCCCCGGAGCCGCCAGGCUUCUAGAGAUAGGCUCCUCAUGUGUCUGCAAUUCCAAAACUUAACAAAAACAAAAAGUUGAGCCUCUGAAGCUGUCACUAACCAAGUGAUUCAGAUGUCGGGACUGGAACACCAGCUGUUGGGGAUGCAGGACUUGGUCUCUGCCCUCCCACACCUCCUGCCUCUUCUUUCUCUCCAUCGCCCCAUCUCUGCCAGUAGAGAAUGGAACUGAGUUGGAGGUCCCCCUCCCCACUAAGUGCCUCUUUGCAUAGCACCAGUCCCCACCCGCACGCUCUCUGGACCACUACAGCUGGACGGGCAAUGGCGGGUCGGGGAGGCGCAGCACGACCCAAUGGACCAGCUGCUGGGAACAAGAUCUGUCAAUUUAAGCUGGUUCUGCUGGGGGAGUCUGCGGUAGGCAAAUCCAGCCUCGUCCUCCGCUUUGUCAAGGGACAGUUUCACGAGUACCAGGAGAGCACAAUUGGAGCGGCCUUCCUCACACAGACUGUCUGCCUGGAUGACACAACAGUCAAGUUUGAGAUCUGGGACACAGCUGGACAGGAGCGGUAUCACAGCCUGGCCCCCAUGUACUAUCGGGGGGCCCAGGCUGCCAUCGUGGUCUAUGACAUCACCAACACAGAUACAUUUGCACGGGCCAAGAACUGGGUGAAGGAGCUACAGAGGCAGGCCAGCCCCAACAUCGUCAUUGCACUCGCGGGUAACAAGGCAGACCUGGCCAGCAAGAGAGCCGUGGAAUUCCAGGAAGCACAAGCCUAUGCAGACGACAACAGUUUGCUGUUCAUGGAGACAUCAGCAAAGACUGCAAUGAACGUGAACGAAAUCUUCAUGGCAAUAGCUAAGAAGCUUCCCAAGAACGAGCCCCAGAAUGCAACUGGUGCUCCAGGCCGAAACCGAGGUGUGGACCUCCAGGAGAACAACCCAGCCAGCCGGAGCCAGUGCUGCAGCAACUGAGCCCCCCUUGCCUGCCCGCUGCCCCCGCCUCCUCCGCCUGAAUGACCCGACUGGAAUCCACUCUAACCAAUCGCACUUAACGACUCGGGCCACCACUGGGGGGGCAGGGGGAGGGGUCCACCAUGAUUUCUCCAUAUAAUUUUGAUCAUAGGCCGGAGUGAGUCAUUCCACCUGCACCUUUCUGUACAAAUACUAAUUCAAUUUUAAGUCUUAAGUCACUUUUUUAAUAUAUAUGAUCUUCUGCUCUUCCCACUUCCUCCCCUUUCUACUGCUCUCCCAUUUUCCCUUGCUGGGAGUAGCCACAUGCUCUUGCCCCCCAACCCUUGUAUAUGGGGACAGUGGGGUCAGUGCAGCUACCCUUUCUUUCCCUCCUGCGGAACAGCGGACCCAGCAAGAGCAUCCACAUCCUCACUUUGUUCGGAGUGGUCUUUGGUUUGGGCGGUGGGGCAGACCUUGGGAAGGGGCUUAGGAAGGGAGAGGCAGCUCUUCCUUCAGCUGGCUCUCAUCAGGCUGCAGCCCCCUCCCCGCUCCCACCUCCCUGCUGGGAAACCACAGCAUUAUCACAGCAUUAUUGUGACAGCCACGAACCCAUUGCCCACAACCCCUCCACCCUCGGUCACCCCAACCUCUGGCUCUGAGCCCUGUUCUGACCAAAUCAUGAUGAUGAGUAUUUGGGGGUGGGUGGGUAAGGGGGGGAGUGGGAGGGGACGGAACCAACUUUUUCUGUAUUUUGUAUUGUAUGUUUUCUUCAACAUGUAACCAAUCAGUAUCUUGUCAAUAUAGUCAGCCGAUCGAUCGACCUCA